AGAGCCAGCAGAGUCCAGGCUGCUGUUAACAACUUCAUGUCCCCGUGGGUAGCAGGCAGGUGCUUCUGUCUGAUCUGGCUCUCCUUGACCACUGUACUCAUCAAAUAGACCAAGAUCCCCAGAGUCCAAGAUCCUUACAAGGGGGCCAGAAAGGGAUGAGCUUUCUGAAGAAGCACUGAUGUAAAAUACCAGGAAUUUUGACAUCGAAGAAGAUUUUUGUGAUGGCAGCUGGGAUUUGGCCAUAAUCUAGAAGACACAUGGUGAAUACAGUUGCAAGUCAUUUAGUCAUAUUUCUUGCUAAAUUGCUGUGUCUUCAAUGGCUGAAUUGAAGAUCCCUCUUACCCGCCAGGUGCCAAGAACUAUGAACAGGCAGGGCAAUAGAAAGACAACUAAAGAAGGAUCCAACGAUUUGAAAUUCCAGAACUUCAGUCUGCCAAAAAACAGGUCAUGGCCUCGCAUCAAUAGUGCCACAGGCCAGUACCAGAGGAUGAACAAGCCUCUUCUAGACUGGGAAAGAAACUUUGCUGCAGUCCUGGAUGGAGCAAAAGGCCACAGUGAUGAUGACUAUGAUGACCCUGAGCUUCGGAUGGAAGAGACAUGGCAGUCGAUUAAAAUUUUACCAGCCCGGCCUAUAAAGGAAUCUGAAUAUGCAGAUACACACUAUUUCAAGGUUGCAAUGGACACUCCCCUUCCGUUAGACACCAGGACCUCUAUCUCCAUUGGACAGCCGACCUGGAACACACAGACGAGGUUGGAAAGAGUGGACAAACCCAUUUCCAAGGACGUCAGAAGCCAAAACAUUAAAGGAGAUGCAUCCGUAAGAAAGAACAAGAUUCCUUUACCACCUCCUCGGCCUCUCAUAACACUUCCGAAGAAGUACCAACCCUUGCCCCCUGAGCCGGAGAGCAGCAGGCCACCUUUAUCUCAGAGACACACCUUUCCAGAAGUCCAGAGAAUGCCCAGUCAGAUAAGCUUAAGGGACUUAAGUGAGGUCCUUGAAGCAGAAAAAGUUCCUCAUAACCAGAGGAAGCCUGAAUCAACUCAUCUGUUAGAAAACCAAAAUACUCAAGAGAUUCCACUUGCCAUUAGCAGUUCUUCAUUCACGACAAGCAACCACAGUGUGCAAAACAGAGAUCAUAGAGGAGGCAUGCAGCCCUGUUCUCCUCAGAGAUGCCAGCCUCCAGCCAGCUGCAGCCCUCACGAAAAUAUACUGCCCUAUAAAUACACAAGCUGGAGACCACCUUUCCCCAAAAGGUCUGAUAGAAAGGAUGUCCAGCACAAUGAAUGGUACAUUGGAGAAUACAGCCGCCAGGCAGUGGAAGAGGCAUUCAUGAAGGAGAACAAGGAUGGUAGUUUCUUGGUCCGAGAUUGUUCCACAAAAUCCAAGGAAGAGCCCUAUGUUUUGGCUGUGUUUUAUGAGAACAAAGUCUACAAUGUAAAAAUACGCUUCCUGGAGAGGAAUCAGCAGUUUGCCCUGGGGACAGGACUCAGAGGAGAUGAGAAGUUUGAUUCAGUAGAAGACAUCAUCGAACACUACAAGAAUUUUCCCAUUAUACUAAUUGAUGGGAAAGAUAAAACUGGGGUCCACAGGAAACAGUGUCACCUCACUCAGCCACUCCCUCUCACCAGACACCUCUUGCCUCUGUAGCCUGGUCUUUGUGUUAUCUUUGGUUUACUGGAUUCAGCGCUUCCAUUGUUUUCAUUGAUUUCAAAAGUUUAUUUUCUGUGCCUUCAAGGGACAACUUUUUUAACUUUGGAGAAAAGAAAAACACUCUAUAACAGAGAGUGGAAAAUCACUCACGGUUUUGAAAGUUCAAACCACAGAGAAAAUAUUUAUAACAUGCAAAAAAUAAAAACAUUCUAGUAACUGGCCACUGGAAAAUAAAUAAAAAUAAAAACUAGGGUUUUAAAAGUAUCUUCUAAAAAACAACAACAAAAAAUACUAUAAACAUAGCCAUUAUGCUCAUGAUACAGGCGAGCAGCAAAGGGCACCAGAAGCUGUUGCUUAAAUGUUUGCAGUCAGUGCAAGACAAGUCUAUGGGAAAUUCCCAAAUCUGUGCUCUUUACAGGACACUGCGCUGCCUUUAUGUCAGUUGUUGGGCCUUACAUAUAUACAAUGUGUGGAUGAUUUCUUACACUAAAGAUGCUGGGCUGGGUGCGGUGCCUCAUGCCUGUAAUCCCAGCACUUUGGGAGGCUGAGGUGGACAGAUCACGAGGUCAGGAGAUCAAGACCAUCCUGGCUAACAUGGUGAAACCCCAUGUCUACUAAAAAUACAAAAAAUCAGCUGGGCGUGGUGGUGGGUGCCUGUAGUCCCAGCUACUCGGGAGGCUGAGGCAGGAGAAUGGUGUGAACCCGGGAGGCGGAGCUUGCAGUGAGCCGAAAUCGCGCCACUGCACUCCAAUCCAGCCUGGGGACAGAGAGACUCCGUCUCAAAAAAAAAAAAAGGUGUUGGGUUGGUGAAUAUUAGCUCUCUUUUAUUGUAAUCCUAGAAAUUCAAGUAUAGGGAAGAAAUGUGGUAUGGAAAACCAGCAAUUGUGAAUGUCACCUUGAAGACAGAAACUGAAAAUCCUCUGACUAGGGUGUGAAACGGUCAUGGGACCAGCCUCCAGCAUCAUCUGCUUCAAGUAGCUUUAAGUCAAAUGGAAUUAACACAUUCAUAGUACAGAGCUCAGAUUAUAUCCUACACUAGCCUUCAGGCAAGCAUAUGUCUGAGGGAAACUAAAAAUUGUAUUAACAAUUCCAAUUAUGGACUUCCAUUCAAAGACAGAGAAAAACUGUCCUCAAAUUAGUGCUAAUUCUUGCAGUAACGUUGCACAGGCCAUGAUAUUAUUCCCUGUAGAGGUUAAGAGGAUUUAAUUUUAUUAUUGUUUUACAAUAAAGAUGAGGAAACAGAGGCUCGAAGUAGCUAUUGAUCUUACUCAAUAUGAGAAGAGAGCCCAGAUUGUAAUCUGCUUUGCCUGGCUCCAUGCAAGCUCAUCUUCCCAGGUACAUUCUCUGCGCUGUGACAUUUUACAAUCAAGUUGAAAAGCUAAUUUAAAAAAAAAGAGAGAGAGAGAGAGAAAGAUAGAAACAAUUUGAAAAUACAGAUUUACCACCUUAAAAUAAAUAAACUCUUCUAGUGGGAAUAAGCUUUUUUAAAAAACAUACUGUCUGUCGAAAAUAACAGUAUAUCAUGAUGUCAAAUGCUACCAAAGCUUACAAAGGAAAUUCAUAGAGUAUUUAUGUAAUUGUAGCAUUGAUGCAGAAAGAAAACCAAAAAUAAUUAAAAGGCAAUAGAAGCAAAUGAAAACAAUAAAAACAAUGUGCAGGAUUAUCUCUUUUGUAAGACAGCAGACAAUGAGCUCUCUGGGAAAAGCUCUUAGCAUCUACCCACUAUCCAAAUACCUGCUCAGGUGUUCUCCUUUCACAAGGUCAAUGUGAAGUGAUGCCUAUAAGUUACAUCAGGAGCAUUUAAUGAAGAAGCUAUUUGUAAAGCUGGAACUUUUGAGACCCAGCUGAGCCUAUCGUAGAGUAUGCCUGCAGAGGAUUACAUAGAACCAAGAGACAAGAGUGUUUAAAUUGGAGCUUGGAUACGAAAGAACUCACUGGUCCGGUCAAAGCUAAAAGCUGUAUGGUUGCUGGUCAUUCUCUACUGGAAUUCAACAAGCCAGGGACAGUAUGGAAACAAGGACUUUACAGAAGAGCUCCAGGCUCACAUUAAGAAGGAAUCUGACCCUCACCCUAAAAAGCUAUUGGGAGAUUACUGAUACCUCCAACUCACUGAUUCAUUGAGGCCAUGCCAUUCAAUGCUAUGUUCUCAAGAAAUGUCUAUGAGUCCUCUCAACCAUUGCUGUUGAUAAAAUAGGUGAAUGUCAAGUGGGGGUUAGCAUUUGAUAAGGUGUACGUUUGAAAUAAUAUUUUAUCGUCUCUUGUUCACAAAUACAACAUAUAAUUCCAAGAAGAAAAAAGAAGUAGAAAUUCAGCAUCCUUAAGAUGACAGCAAGAAUGAGGGGAAAAGGAAGAAAAAAAAGAAAUUAAACAUCUUGCAAUAAAAAGCUUACAAUAUUUUUGUGUAUUUGAACACUUCUGUAAAAAAUAUAAAAUGGAAAAUACUGACAUGGGCUGCUUCUGGUGAUUGGGGUUUGAGGGAUUGGGUGUCGGGUUUUCUAGAACUCAGACACCAGGACAAAGUUAGAAGUGCAAACACUGAUUGGAGGUUAAUGUUUGAGAAAGAUAAAAGGGAGAAGAAACAGAAGUAUGGGUAUGGGGUGGGCUUUCAGGCUCCCACCUGUGAGAGGGAAGAGGGGAGGUGUGGGGAGUGAGGAGAAAAAGCAUGAGAUUCAGACACAGCUCUGGGAGAGUUUUGGCCAGCUCAUAGUGAGGCCCAAAGCAAAGUUUGCCCAGAGAGGAGACAGUGUUAUGCUGGGCAGUAAUGUCUGGGUCUUAGUGCCCCAUCCUGUUAAGUCAUUGUCUGGGGCUAUCCUGGGAAAAAGAAAAACAACAAAAAAAAAAGACCUGCAAAUGCUGUGGCCAAUCCAGAAGGCGCAGCUGGACGCUGUCCACUAACUUGCUGGCCAGCAAGUUAUUUCAAUGGAGACUCAAGAGACCCACCUCUGGCCUGCCACAGCAACAUCCUGAAUUCACUGUUUUCAGUGUUGAUUGUAGUAAGGACAAUCACAUUUACAUUUUGCUUGUAAUGGAUGAUUAAAUAAUAAGAGUAUAUAAAUUCGAUUGUAUUUGUUUCUUACAACACUUCUGUAAAGAAGAGAGGGCAGCUAUUUCUAAUGCAUUUUAUAAUUGAGGAAAUUGUACCUCAUUGGCCAAAAUCUCACAGUGACAUAGUCGCGACUGGAACCAAGGUCUCCAUAUGCAAUUAUCCUAUUCAUGGUCUACCUGCUUUAUUAGAUCUGUAAUUGAAUAUUCAAUGAUUUGGAUUUGGCAUGCCCAAAUUCCAGUGUUUUAAUCCCUUUUCAACCAUUACCUCACGUUUAGUUUAAAAGUAUCACUUGAUAUCUGAUUUCAAUAGAGUAAUAGAAUUUUAGCUUUAUCCAAUUACAGCAUUUAUGCUUUCCAGAUAUUUUUUGGACUAAAUAAUUCUCAUUCUGUAUAAAUGUGCAUAGCCCUCAUCAUUAGUCAUAUAUUGUGUUAGCACCUUUGUGUACUGCAUGUGUAUUCAUUACUAAGCACUAUUGUAGAUGUUGAAAAUAGAGCAGUGAAUAAGAGAGAUAGAUGACAAAUAAAUAUACAAACAAAUAAGAUAAUCUAAGUCAGUUUCCCAUUACUGGAUUGGAUUUCUAUUUUAACACUUAUUUCUGAGUACUUGUGGGGUGAUGCCAACAUUAAAUGUUUUGAGGAAGCUCCUUUGAGAUGGCUUUGAAAAGUCCUAAGUGAGAAAAUUUAAAAUUUUCCCAAACUUAUUUAUGUGGGGUGUGCAUGUGUGUGCCUGUGCCUGUGUGCGUGUGUGUGUGUGUGUUUUUAAGUAACCGCAUCAUGGCUGUAAUCAGUUAAGUCUCCUGUUCUAAUUACUACGGAGGAAUCAAAUGAACCCCAUUGUCGAAUGUAGCCAAUUAUGUAUGUGUGUACACAAAUACAAAUUUUUAUGAUAGCCUAUAUUGUAUAUUAGCAUUAUAUUUGUAUAUCUUUUUUAUUCUGAGCAAUAUUUGUUCUAGCUAAGCACAUUUACAUUCAUAAUUUACAGCCUUACUAAUGUAAAUAAAAGUAAAUAUGUAAUUGAAUGUUA